ACUUCCGGAACAAGCGUCGCGUUUCUGAGGAGAAACUCUUGGUGAGAAUUCCCAGAGUGAUAAUGGCUACCUACAGCCUGGCGAACGAGAGACUACGCGCUCUGGAAGACAUUGAACGGGAAAUCGGCGCCAUCCUUCAGAAUGCAGGUACUGUGAUCCUAGAAUUGUCCAAGGAAAAAACUAACGAGCGGCUCCUAGACCGGCAGGCGGCGGCCUUCACCGCUUCAGUGCAACACGUGGAGGCGGAGCUGUCAGCUCAGAUCCGCUACCUCACCCAGCUACCAGAUGGCCUAACAAAUUCAAACUCAGGGAAGAAAUGAGACGAGACCUGAUGCCUGGUUGGAGUUAGGGUAAAGGAGAUGGUGCUCCAUUGAUAGUCUGUCUUGUAGGUGGCCACAGGGCAGCCCCAUGAGGGCUCCAGCUACUCUUCGAGGAAGGACUGUCAGAUGGCUCUGAAGCGAGUGGACUAUGCCCGCCUCAAGCUCAGUGAUGUGGCUCGAACCUGUGAGCAGAUGCUGGAGAACUAGGCCAGGGAGAUGGACCCAGAGCUGAGAGGGAGACCAUCACCUGUGCCAUGGGACAGAACCUGGGAACAUGUAGGGUGGGGAGUAUGAGCACCAACAUACCCUGCUGGUCAAAGUACCCUAGGACAAAGGGGCAAAUGGUGGGCAUGGAAAAACUGAAGCCCGAGCCUGCCCACAGCUAUGCUUUGGCCUCUCCAGCAGGGUGCUCCUGCUCUGCACUCCAGAAACACCCUGACAGGCUCAGAGAGGAGAUGGAAACUGACAUACCCAACCCACUUCCUCAAACACUUCAUGCUGCUGCCCCAGCCUUCCCGCAGACUUGGCCUAAUGAAAAUACAUACUUCUUCAUUCGGAGAGACAAAACAAGAACUAGAGUUUUAAUGAUAAUAAAAGCAAUAAUAAUAAAAGCAAUAACAAUAAAAA